AGUUGGGAGCAGGCGACGCCGACGCGAGUCUGGCGGCUGCUGCUUGCGACUGCGGAGGCCGGGCGAGGCCGGUGAGGACGCGGCGGGCGAGCGAGAGGCCGAGGUGUUUUCUUCACUCAUGGUGAAGAAUGGGGGAGAUAGAAGGAACAUACAGAGUCCUGCAGACUGCAGGGAUGCGCUUGGGUGCCCAGACCCCUGUGGGAGUUAGCACCCUUGAGCCUGGGCAGACUCUCUUGCCCAGAAUGCAAGAGAAGCACCUGCACCUCAGAGUAAAGCUGCUGGACAACACCAUGGAAAUAUUUGACAUUGAGCCUAAAUGCGAUGGCCAGGUAUUACUGACACAAGUGUGGAAGCGUUUAAACCUGGUAGAAUGUGACUACUUCGGGAUGGAGUUUCAAAAUACUCAGUCCUACUGGAUUUGGCUUGAACCUAUGAAACCCAUCAUUAGGCAAAUACGAAGGCCAAAGAAUGUGGUGCUUCGCCUAGCUGUAAAAUUUUUUCCACCUGAUCCUGGUCAGCUACAAGAAGAAUAUACAAGAUACUUGUUUGCCUUGCAACUUAAGAGAGACCUGCUGGAAGAGCGUUUGACCUGUGCUGACACCACAGCGGCCCUUCUCACGUCCCAUCUCCUGCAGUCGGAAAUAGGAGAUUACGAUGAAACGCUGGACCGAGAGCACCUCAAAGUGAACGAGUAUUUGCCUGGCCAGCAGCACUGCCUUGAGAAGAUACUAGAAUUCCAUCAGAAGCACGUGGGCCAGACACCUGCUGAGUCGGAUUUCCAGGUGCUCGAAAUUGCUCGAAAGUUGGAAAUGUACGGCAUCAGAUUUCACAUGGCUUCUGACAGGGAAGGAACCAAGAUUCAACUGGCAGUUUCCCACAUGGGUGUACUCGUGUUCCAGGGCACCACCAAAAUCAACACUUUCAACUGGUCCAAGGUCCGUAAACUAAGCUUCAAGAGGAAAAGAUUUCUUAUCAAACUUCAUCCAGAGGUUCAUGGACCUUACCAGGACACAUUAGAAUUUUUGUUGGGUAGUAGAGAUGAAUGUAAGAACUUCUGGAAGAUUUGUGUGGAGUAUCACACCUUUUUUAGACUUUUGGACCAACCUAAGCCAAAAGCAAAAGCCGUCUUCUUCAGCCGGGGCUCCUCCUUCAGAUACAGUGGAAGAACUCAGAAACAACUAGUAGAUUAUUUCAAAGACAGUGGAAUGAAGAGAAUUCCAUAUGAAAGAAGGCACAGCAAGACCCACACGUCCGUUCGAGCUCUGACUGCAGACCUACCAAAACAGAGCAUCUCAUUCCCCGAGGGAUUGAGGACUCCUGCCUCCCCAUCUUCAGCGAAUGCCUUUUACUCGCUCUCUCCCUCCACUCUGGUCCCCUCUGGCCUGCCAGAGUUUAAGGACAGCAGCAGCUCCCUCACAGAUCCCCAGGUUUCCUACGUCAAGAGUCCAGCUGCAGAGAGGCGCAGUGGAGCAGUGGCUGGAGGCCCCGACACACCAUCGGCCCAGCCCCUCGGGCCCCCCGCACUCCAGCCUGGUCCAGGCCUUUCCACGAAGAGUCCUCAGCCUUCUCCCUCCAGCCGGAAGAGCCCCCUGAGUCUGAGCCCUGCAUUUCAGGUGCCUUUGGGCCCAGCUGAACAGGGCUCAUCCCCACUCCUGAGCCCUGUCCUCAGUGAUGCUGGCGGAGCCGGGAUGGACUGCGAGGAGCCCAGACACAAGCGCGUGCCUGCAGACGAGGCCUACUUCAUAGUCAAAGAGAUUCUCGCUACAGAACGAACAUACCUCAAGGAUUUAGAAGUUAUUACCGUGUGGUUCCGCAGCGCAGUGGUGAAGGAGGACGCCAUGCCUGCGACUCUGAUGACGCUGCUCUUCUCCAACAUCGAUCCCAUCUAUGAGUUCCACAGAGGCUUCCUGCGCGAGGUGGAGCAGAGGCUGGCACUCUGGGAAGGGCCCUCCAAAGCCCACACAAAAGGCAGUCAUCAACGAAUCGGGGACAUCCUGCUCAGGAACAUGCGCCAGUUAAAGGAGUUUACCAGCUACUUCCAAAGACAUGACGAGGUCCUAACAGAACUGGAAAAGGCUACCAAACGCUGUAAGAAGUUGGAGGCAGUGUACAAGGAGUUUGAGCUGCAGAAGGUCUGCUACUUGCCUCUCAACACGUUCCUGCUGAAGCCCAUCCAGCGGCUGCUGCACUACCGCCUGCUGCUGCGCCGCCUAUGCGGACAUUACAGCCCCGGGCACCAUGACUACGCUGACUGCCAUGACGCCCUGAAAGCCAUCACAGAGGUGACCACCACACUACAGCACAUUCUCAUCCGGCUGGAGAACCUGCAGAAGCUAACGGAGCUGCAGCGGGACCUGGUGGGCAUAGAGAACCUCAUUGCUCCUGGCAGGGAGUUCAUCCGUGAGGGCUGCCUUCACAAGCUCACCAAGAAGGGCCUGCAGCAGAGGAUGUUUUUUCUGUUCUCAGAUAUGUUGCUGUACACAAGCAAAGGAGUUGCAGGGACCAGCCACUUCCGGAUCCGGGGCCUCCUUCCCCUCCAAGGCAUGCUGCUAAUAGUGCUGGACCCCCCGGUGGAAGAAAGUGAUAACGAGUGGUCUGUUCCACACUGUUUCACCAUCUACGCGGCUCAGAAAACAAUCGUGGUGGCAGCCAGCACUCGGCUGGAGAAAGAGAAGUGGAUGCUGGACCUGAACUCCGCGAUCCAAGCAGCCAAGAGUGGCGGUGACACGGCCCCUGCACUGCCAGGCCGCACUGUGUGCACUCGUCCCCCCAGAUCCCCCAACGAGGUAUCUCUGGAGCAGGAGUCAGAAGAUGAUGCUCGGGGUGUCCGCAGCUCCCUGGAGGGGCAUGGCCAGCACCGGGCCAACACCACAAUGCACGUGUGCUGGUACCGGAACACCAGCGUGUCCAGGGCAGACCACAGUGCAGCUGUCGAGAACCAGCUUUCAGGAUAUCUGCUAAGAAAGUUCAAAAACAGUCAUGGCUGGCAGAAGCUCUGGGUCGUCUUUACCAACUUCUGUUUGUUCUUCUACAAAACUCAUCAGGAUGACUACCCACUGGCCAGCCUCCCGCUGCUGGGCUACAGCGUGAGCAUCCCCAGGGAGGCCGAUGGCAUACACAAAGACUAUGUUUUCAAGCUCCAGUUCAAAUCCCACGUCUACUUCUUCCGGGCUGAGAGCAAGUACACAUUUGAAAGGUAAUUUUGCAGGAGGCAGCCCUGGUCAGCUGCCCAUUUCGAUGUCCGCUCAGCUCCCAUUUCUACUCAUGGUGGUGGAGGCAAGUUUUCUGGGCCCUGGAAAGGAAGGGCUGAGCAAUGCUUCCAGCAUUUCCAAAAAACAGCAAUGCUUUGUUUUUUUUUUUUUUGGAGAUGGCGUCUCCCUCUGUCACUCAGGCUGGAGUGCAGUGAUACAAUCUUGGCUCACUAUAACCUGCACCUCCAGGGUUCAAGCGAUUCUUCUGCCUCAGCCUCCUGAGUAACUGAGAUUACAGGCAUGCACGCCACGCCGCCUGGCUAAUUUUUGUAUUUUUAGUAGAGACAGGGUUUCACCAUGUUGGCCAGGCUGGUCUCGAACUCCUGACCUCAAGUGAUCCAUCUGCCUCAGCCUCCCAAAGUGCUGGGAUUAUAGGCAUGAGCCACCGCACCCGGCCCCAGGUUUUUAACCCUUCUUUUGUCCUGCUUGUCCCAUAUCCUGGGUUGUUCUUGGGACAGUGUCUGAGCACAAGAUGGCUCACUGGUCUGAUGGCCGCCCUCUCCUCCAGGUGGAUGGAGGUGAUCCAGGGGGCCAGCAGCUCAGCCGGGAGGGCCCCAAGCAUCGUGCAGGAUGGCCCCCAACCCUCCUCAGGGCUGGAGGGGAUGGUCAGGGGGAAGGAGGAAUGACGCUCAACCUGCCCAGGUUUGGACACAACUACAAAGAACAGCAGGACACAGAGGUGACCUCUGUCCUGAGGCUUCUCAACAGAUGGGAAGUGGCUGUGGUCUCACUGGAUCCCCACUGGCACCAGCAGUGUGGGUGGGCCUCAUGUAACAUCUGGGAGGGGCUUCAUCCCCCCACCCAGGACCUAGUGCAUGCCAGCAGCUAUCUGGGGCCCUGGGAAAAAUGUGCGAGUCUUGAGCGCGGAGCCGCUCAAGCCACAGCUCCCAGGCCCCUGGCUCAAAGACGCAGACAAGGCCUGAGCAGUGCUCUCGGCAUCGGACCAAAGCCUGGGCACACCCUGCCUCUCUCCCCAGAGCAGGGUCCCUGCCGAGGACUGGCCUAGAGCAAGCACUGGAAAAGAGGCCCUGCCAUACACCCUGCGUACCCACUGCCAGGACCCUCUCAGACAAGCGUGGCACAGCCAUGCUGACCUUCCAUCUGGUGAACCAAGUGGCAGCCCCAGGGGCCUGCCCUGCAGGUCACAGCUAAACAAGUCUGGCAGAAGCCACGCUUGUUCCCCAUGUACCUCUAGAGAAGCAGAAACCAAAGUCCCCCUGUGCCCUGGGAGGGUGGGGCCGUCUAAUUUAUUACUGCCCAGCAUUCCUUCCAACGGGAAGUAGAUGGGCGACUGCUUUGUUCACACACAUUUGAUUAAAAAUAAACAAACAGCAUCUCCCCA